CUUCGGGCGCUGACAGGGAGAGCCUGGGGCCGGGCCGUGUGGAUGCCAUCCCCGAGCGCGGUUCGCGCUCGGCUGAGGCGCUGGACAAGUGGCUUGGGCUCCCGCGCCUCAGUUUCUCUCUGUGGCGCCGCCUACCUCACAGACUUGUGAGCACUCACUGACGUGGGUAGCGCCCAGGGCCUGCGGGGCGCAGGAGAGCUGGAGUCAGGCGGAGACCGCAGGCUGACCCCGCAGCGGCCGGGCUGUCGCGGCCCCCACCUCAGGUAACCAUGUGCGACCGAAAGGCCGUGAUCAAAAAUGCGGACAUGUCGGAAGAGAUGCAACAGGACUCGGUGGAGUGCGCUACUCAGGCGCUGGAGAAAUACAACAUAGAGAAGGACAUUGCGGCUCAUAUCAAGAAGGAAUUUGACAAGAAGUACAAUCCCACCUGGCAUUGCAUCGUGGGGAGGAACUUCGGUAGUUAUGUGACACAUGAAACCAAACACUUCAUCUACUUCUACCUGGGCCAAGUGGCCAUUCUUCUGUUCAAAUCUGGUUAAAAGCAUGGACUGUGCCACACACCCAGUGAUCCAUCCAAAAACAAGGACUGCAGCCUAAAUUCCAAAUACCAGAGACUGAAAUUUUCAGCCUUGCUAAGGGAACAUCUCGAUGUUUGAACCUUUGUUGUGUUUUGUACAGGGCAUUCUCUGUACUAGUUUGUCGUGGUUAUAAAACAAUUAGCAGAAUAGCCUACAUUUGUAUUUAUUUUCUAUUCCAUACUUCUGCCCACGUUGUUUUCUCUCAAAAUCCAUUCCUUUAAAAAAUAAAUCUGAUGCAGAUGUG